UUUCUCGCAUCCCGGCACGCUGGUGAAGUUGUAAAAGUCACAAAUGGUGGGCUAGAGAUGAGGGUUUCUGUUGAGGCAGCAGGCCCAGAAAGGUGGGGUAAGGCCAAGCUAGUGGGGCCAGCAUGAGACCCUGCCUGCCAGCUUUCCUGUGAAGGAUUAAUUAACCUCCCCAGAUUCUGCUGUUACAAGGAAAAGAAGGUUUAAGGAAAGGAAUAGUUAAGUUACUACCCCUGUGACUCAUCUACACUGAGGAAAAAGCCCGUGAUGAUUUUGGAGUCCUGAUUCUGGAUAGUGCCUUUGCCCAAGUUGUAGGCUAACAAUUGCAGAGUUGCCAUGGUUAGAUAGCCAAUGGUGGGAUCACUUAAUUGCCACCCCUUGUUGUGGGUUUAUUAUAUGCCAGCACCACAUUAAACUCUUUAUGUAUGUUAAUUUGUAAAUGAACAUACUUAAUCCCCCUAAGAGCUGCAUUUUACAAAGAAGAUAAUAAGGUAUAAUUCCCUUAGAAAAGAACCACCCCUUCUUUUUCUAAAAGCCUUAAAGAACUAUUGGAUUUUGACCCAAGAAAACCUGAAUAGUACGGCAGCAAAAUUGGGUUAGAGUUACAUAUAGGCAAAAAUCAGAGUUCUAGAUAGGACAAGAGUUGAAGACAUCCAUUAACUUAAAAGUAAUUAAGGCUGGGUGUGGUGGCUCACACCUGUAAUCCCAACACUGGGAGGCCAAGGUGGGAAGAUCUUUUGAUGCCAGGAGUUCCACAAUAGCCUGGGCAAAAAAUAAAUUAAGAGCAAUUAAGAUGUUGGAUUCAGAAGUGUUUUAACCUGGGACAAUCUGAGUUCAGUUCAUUUAAUGAAGUGGUAUUUAAUAGCCCUAAGCAUUCACUGAGUAUUUCAGCCUGUGACAUAUUAGAAAGCAUGUAACUUAAAAGAUCCAAGUUCAAGUCUAUCCUCUACCACUACCACAGUUUCAAGACUGGGUUUAGGGUCACGCUCUUGCGUUAAGUAUACCUAAUAAUCAUCUGGGAAACUUGUUUGAAAUACAGGGCACUUGAGCCUUAUUCCCAGAGAUCUUUUUUGUUUGUUUAUAGACAGGGUUUCACGUUGUUGCCCAUACUGGACAACUGGCGUGAUCAUAGCUCACUGAAGCCUCCAGCUCCUGGGUUCAAGCAGUCCUCCUGCCUCAGCUUCUGGAGUAGCUGGGACUACAGGUGCACUUCCACCUCACCUGGCUAAUUUUAUGUUUUGUAGAGAUGAGGUCUUGAUGUUUGCCCAGGCUGGUCUCAAACUCCUGGCUUCAAGUUAUCUUUCCGCCCCAGCUUCUCAGUGUUGGGAUUACAGGAAUGAGCCACUGAACCUAGCUCCCCCAGAGAUCUUGACCAGGAAGGUCCAAGUUGCGCCCAAGAAUAUGCAUUUUUUAAUACGUACACCACCCAGAUAAUUCUAGUUCAGAUGGGCUUCUCACUUCACUUGGAGAAACCCUGCCUUUAGGUUUUUAACUCACCUUCUGUUUGAGCUCUCCUGCCACAGCUCCUCACCCCCUGAAAAUGUUCGCCUGCUCCAAGUUUGUCUCCACUCCCUCCUUGGUCAAGAGCACCUCACAGCUGCUGAGCCGUCCGCUAUCUGCAGUGGUGCUGAAACGACCGGAGAUACUGACAGAUGAGAGCCUCAGCAGCUUGGCAGUCUCAUGUCCCCUUACCUCACUUGUCUCUAGCCGCAGCUUCCAAACCAGCGCCAUUUCAAGGGACAUCGACACAGCAGCCAAGUUCAUUGGAGCUGGGGCUGCCACAGUUGGGGUGGCUGGUUCUGGGGCUGGGAUUGGAACUGUGUUUGGGAGCCUCAUCAUUGGUUAUGCCAGGAACCCUUCUCUGAAGCAACAGCUCUUCUCCUACGCCAUUCUGGGCUUUGCCCUCUCGGAGGCCAUGGGGCUCUUUUGUCUGAUGGUAGCCUUUCUCAUCCUCUUUGCCAUGUGAAGGAGCCGUCUCCACCUCCCAUAGUUCUCCCGCGUCUGGUUGGCCCCGUGUGUUCCUUUUCCUAUACCUCCCCAGGCAGCCUGGGGAACGUGGUUGGCUCAGGGUUUGACAGAGAAAAGACAAAUAAAUACUGUAUUAAUAAGA